AAGCUCAGCGCACUUGGCUUAAGGGGCGGCGCGCUCCCUGCCUGCUGCUGGGCGGAGGGAAGGCGGCAAGAGCUGCGGAGCCCCUGGAAGAGCUUCCAGGAACCCUGCGCUGUGGGAUAAAGGAAUGAGGUUCAGAAAGGGGCAGGGAGUUGCCCGCAGCCGCACCGCACGUCUUCAGCCCGACCGUUGUCCUGACCUCUCUGUCCCGUCCCCUGCCCAGUCUCACCAUGGCCUUCUGGACACAGCUGAUGCUGCUGCUCUGGAAGAAUUUCAUGUAUCGCCGGAGACAGCCGGUCCAGCUCCUGGUCGAAUUGCUGUGGCCUCUCUUCCUCUUCUUCAUCCUGGUGGCUGUUCGCCACUCCCACCCGCCCCUGGAGCACCAUGAAUGCCACUUCCCAAACAAGCCACUGCCAUCGGCGGGCACCGUGCCCUGGCUCCAGGGUCUCAUCUGUAAUGUGAACAACACCUGCUUUCCGCAGCUGACACCGGGCGAGGAGCCCGGGCGCCUGAGCAACUUCAACGACUCCCUGGUCUCCCGGCUGCUAGCCGAUGCCCGCACUGUGCUGGGAGGGGCCAGUGCCCACAGGACGCUGGCUGGCCUAGGGAAGCUGAUCGCCACGCUGAGGGCUGCACGCAGCACGGCCCAGCCUCAACCAACCAAGCAGUCUCCACUGGAACCACCCAUGCUGGAUGUCGCGGAGCUGCUGACGUCACUGCUGCGCACGGAAUCCCUGGGGUUGGCACUGGGCCAAGCCCAGGAGCCCUUGCACAGCUUGUUGGAGGCCGCUGAGGACCUGGCCCAGGAGCUCCUGGCGCUGCGCAGCCUGGUGGAGCUUCGGGCACUGCUGCAGAGACCCCGAGGGACCAGCGGCCCCCUGGAGUUGCUGUCAGAGGCCCUCUGCAGUGUCAGGGGACCUAGCAGCACAGUGGGCCCCUCCCUCAACUGGUACGAGGCUAGUGACCUGAUGGAGCUGGUGGGGCAGGAGCCAGAAUCCGCCCUGCCAGACAGCAGCCUGAGCCCCGCCUGCUCGGAGCUGAUUGGAGCCCUGGACAGCCACCCGCUGUCCCGCCUGCUCUGGAGACGCCUGAAGCCUCUGAUCCUCGGGAAGCUACUCUUUGCACCAGAUACACCUUUUACCCGGAAGCUCAUGGCCCAGGUGAACCGGACCUUCGAGGAGCUCACCCUGCUGAGGGAUGUCCGGGAGGUGUGGGAGAUGCUGGGACCCCGGAUCUUCACCUUCAUGAACGACAGUUCCAAUGUGGCCAUGCUGCAGCGGCUCCUGCAGAUGCAGGAUGAAGGAAGAAGGCAGCCCAGACCUGGAGGCCGGGACCACAUGGAGGCCCUGCGAUCCUUUCUGGACCCUGGGAGCGGUGGCUACAGCUGGCAGGACGCACACGCUGAUGUGGGGCACCUGGUGGGCACGCUGGGCCGAGUGACGGAGUGCCUGUCCUUGGACAAGCUGGAGGCGGCACCCUCAGAGGCAGCCCUGGUGUCGCGGGCCCUGCAACUGCUCGCGGAACAUCGAUUCUGGGCCGGCGUCGUCUUCUUGGGACCUGAGGACUCUUCAGACCCCACAGAGCACCCAACCCCAGACCUGGGCCCCGGCCACGUGCGCAUCAAAAUCCGCAUGGACAUUGACGUGGUCACGAGGACCAAUAAGAUCAGGGACAGGUUUUGGGACCCUGGCCCAGCCGCGGACCCCCUGACCGACCUGCGCUACGUGUGGGGCGGCUUCGUGUACCUGCAAGACCUGGUGGAGCGUGCAGCCGUCCGCGUGCUCAGCGGCGCCAACCCCCGGGCCGGCCUCUACCUGCAGCAGAUGCCCUAUCCGUGCUAUGUGGACGACGUGUUCCUGCGUGUGCUGAGCCGGUCGCUGCCGCUCUUCCUGACGCUGGCCUGGAUCUACUCCGUGACACUGACAGUGAAGGCCGUGGUGCGGGAGAAGGAGACGCGGCUGCGGGACACCAUGCGCGCCAUGGGGCUCAGCCGCGCGGUGCUCUGGCUAGGCUGGUUCCUCAGCUGCCUCGGGCCCUUCCUGCUCAGCGCCGCACUGCUGGUUCUGGUGCUCAAGCUGGGAGACAUCCUCCCCUACAGCCACCCGGGCGUGGUCUUCCUGUUCUUGGCAGCCUUCGCGGUGGCCACGGUGACCCAGAGCUUCCUGCUCAGCGCCUUCUUCUCCCGCGCCAACCUGGCUGCGGCCUGCGGCGGCCUGGCCUACUUCUCCCUCUACCUGCCCUACGUGCUGUGUGUGGCUUGGCGGGACCGGCUGCCCGCGGGUGGCCGCGUGGCCGCGAGCCUGCUGUCGCCCGUGGCCUUCGGCUUCGGCUGCGAGAGCCUGGCUCUGCUGGAGGAGCAGGGCGAGGGCGCGCAGUGGCACAACGUGGGCACCCGGCCUACGGCAGACGUCUUCAGCCUGGCCCAGGUCUCUGGCCUUCUGCUGCUGGACGCGGCGCUCUACGGCCUCGCCACCUGGUACCUGGAAGCUGUGUGCCCAGGCCAGUACGGGAUCCCUGAACCAUGGAAUUUUCCUUUUCGGAGGAGCUACUGGUGCGGACCUCGGCCCCCCAAGAGUCCAGCCCCUUGCCCCACCCCGCUGGACCCAAAGGUGCUGGUAGAAGAGGCACCGCCCGGCCUGAGUCCUGGCGUCUCCGUUCGCAGCCUGGAGAAGCGCUUUCCUGGAAGCCCGCAGCCAGCCCUGCGGGGGCUCAGCCUGGACUUCUACCAGGGCCACAUCACCGCCUUCCUGGGCCACAACGGGGCCGGCAAGACCACCACCCUGUCCAUCUUGAGUGGCCUCUUCCCACCCAGUGGUGGCUCUGCCUUCAUCCUGGGCCACGACGUCCGCUCCAGCAUGGCCGCCAUCCGGCCCCACCUGGGCGUCUGUCCUCAGUACAACGUGCUGUUUGACAUGCUGACCGUGGACGAGCACGUCUGGUUCUAUGGGCGGCUGAAGGGUCUGAGUGCCGCUGUAGUGGGCCCCGAGCAGGACCGUCUGCUGCAGGAUGUGGGGCUGGUCUCCAAGCAGAGUGUGCAGACUCGCCACCUCUCUGGUGGGAUGCAACGGAAGCUGUCCGUGGCCAUUGCCUUUGUGGGCGGCUCCCAAGUUGUUAUCCUGGACGAGCCUACGGCUGGCGUGGAUCCUGCUUCCCGCCGCGGUAUUUGGGAGCUGCUGCUCAAAUACCGAGAAGGUCGCACGCUGAUCCUCUCCACCCACCACCUGGAUGAGGCAGAGCUGCUGGGAGACCGUGUGGCCGUGGUGGCAGGUGGCCGCUUGUGCUGCUGUGGCUCCCCACUCUUCCUGCGCCGUCACCUGGGCUCCGGCUACUACCUGACGCUGGUGAAGGCCCGCCUGCCCCUGACCACCAAUGAGAAGGCUGACACUGACAUGGAGGGCAGUGUGGACACCAGGCAGGAAAAGAAGAAUGGCAGCCAGGGCAGCAGAGUCGGCACUCCUCAGCUGCUGGCCCUGGUACAGCACUGGGUGCCCGGGGCACGGCUGGUGGAGGAGCUGCCACACGAGCUGGUGCUGGUGCUGCCCUACACGGGUGCCCAUGACGGCAGCUUCGCCACACUCUUCCGAGAGCUAGACACGCGGCUGGCGGAGCUGAGGCUCACUGGCUACGGGAUCUCCGACACCAGCCUCGAGGAGAUCUUCCUGAAGGUGGUGGAGGAGUGUGCUGCGGACACAGAUAUGGAGGAUGGCAGCUGCGGGCAGCACCUAUGCACAGGCAUUGCUGGCCUAGACGUAACCCUACGGCUCAAGAUGCCGCCACAGGAGACAGCGCUGGAGAACGGGGAACCAGCUGGGUCAGCCCCAGAGACUGACCAGGGCUCUGGGCCAGACGCCGUGGGCCGGGUACAGGGCUGGGCACUGACCCGCCAGCAGCUCCAGGCCCUGCUUCUCAAGCGCUUUCUGCUUGCCCGCCGCAGCCGCCGCGGCCUGUUCGCCCAGAUCGUGCUGCCUGCCCUCUUUGUGGGCCUGGCCCUCGUGUUCAGCCUCAUCGUGCCUCCUUUCGGGCACUACCCGGCUCUGCGGCUCAGUCCCACCAUGUACGGUGCUCAGGUGUCCUUCUUCAGUGAGGACGCCCCAGGGGACCCUGGACGUGCCCGGCUGCUCGAGGCGCUGCUGCAGGAGGCAGGACUGGAGGAGCCCCCAGUGCAGCAUAGCUCCCACAGGUUCUCGGCACCAGAAGUUCCUGCUGAAGUGGCCAAGGUCUUGGCCAGUGGCAACUGGACCCCAGAGUCUCCAUCCCCAGCCUGCCAGUGUAGCCGGCCCGGUGCCCGGCGCCUGCUGCCCGACUGCCCGGCUGCAGCUGGUGGUCCCCCUCCGCCCCAGGCAGUGACCGGCUCUGGGGAAGUGGUUCAGAACCUGACAGGCCGGAACCUGUCUGACUUCCUGGUCAAGACCUACCCGCGCCUGGUGCGCCAGGGCCUGAAGACUAAGAAGUGGGUGAAUGAGGUCAGAUACGGAGGCUUCUCGCUGGGGGGCCGAGACCCAGGCCUGCCCUCGGGCCAAGAGUUGGGCCGCUCAGUGGAGGAGUUGUGGGCGCUGCUGAGUCCCCUGCCUGGCGGGGCCCUCGACCGUGUCCUGAAAAACCUCACAGCCUGGGCUCACAGCCUGGAUGCUCAGGACAGUCUCAAGAUCUGGUUCAACAACAAAGGCUGGCACUCCAUGGUGGCCUUUGUCAACCGAGCCAGCAACGCAAUCCUCCGUGCUCACCUGCCCCCAGGCCCGGCCCGCCACGCCCACAGCAUCACCACACUCAACCACCCCUUGAACCUCACCAAGGAGCAGCUGUCUGAGGGUGCACUGAUGGCCUCCUCGGUGGACGUCCUCGUCUCCAUCUGUGUGGUCUUUGCCAUGUCCUUUGUCCCGGCCAGCUUCACUCUUGUCCUCAUUGAGGAGCGAGUCACCCGAGCCAAGCACCUGCAGCUCAUGGGGGGCCUGUCCCCCACCCUCUACUGGCUUGGCAACUUUCUCUGGGACAUGUGUAACUACUUGGUGCCAGCAUGCAUCGUGGUGCUCAUCUUUCUGGCCUUCCAGCAGAGGGCAUAUGUGGCCCCUGCCAACCUGCCUGCUCUCCUGCUGUUGCUACUACUGUAUGGCUGGUCGAUCACACCGCUCAUGUACCCAGCCUCCUUCUUCUUCUCCGUGCCCAGCACAGCCUAUGUGGUGCUCACCUGCAUAAACCUCUUUAUUGGCAUCAAUGGAAGCAUGGCCACCUUUGUGCUUGAGCUCUUCUCUGAUCAGAAGCUGCAGGAGGUGAGCCGGAUCUUGAAACAGGUCUUCCUUAUCUUCCCCCACUUCUGCUUGGGCCGGGGGCUCAUUGACAUGGUGCGGAACCAGGCCAUGGCUGAUGCCUUUGAGCGCUUGGGAGACAGGCAGUUCCAGUCACCCCUGCGCUGGGAGGUGGUCGGCAAGAACCUCUUGGCCAUGGUGAUACAGGGGCCCCUCUUCCUUCUCUUCACACUACUGCUGCAGCACCGAAGCCAACUCCUGCCACAGCCCAGGGUGAGGUCUCUGCCACUCCUGGGAGAGGAGGACGAGGAUGUAGCCCGUGAACGGGAGCGGGUGGUCCAAGGAGCCACCCAGGGGGAUGUGUUGGUGCUGAGGAACUUGACCAAGGUAUACCGUGGGCAGAGGAUGCCAGCUGUUGACCGCUUGUGCCUGGGGAUUCCCCCUGGUGAGUGUUUUGGGCUGCUGGGUGUGAAUGGAGCAGGGAAGACGUCCACGUUUCGCAUGGUGACGGGGGACACAUUGGCCAGCAGGGGCGAGGCUGUGCUGGCAGGCCACAGCGUGGCCCGGGAACCCAGUGCUGCGCACCUCAGCAUGGGAUACUGCCCUCAAUCCGAUGCCAUCUUUGAGCUGCUGACGGGCCGCGAGCACCUGGAGCUGCUUGCGCGCCUGCGCGGUGUCCCGGAGGCCCAGGUUGCCCAGACCGCUGGCUCGGGCCUGGCGCGUCUGGGACUCUCAUGGUACGCAGACCGGCCUGCAGGCACCUACAGCGGAGGGAACAAACGCAAGCUGGCGACGGCCCUGGCGCUGGUUGGGGACCCAGCCGUGGUGUUUCUGGACGAGCCGACCACAGGCAUGGACCCCAGCGCGCGGCGCUUCCUUUGGAACAGCCUUUUGGCCGUGGUGCGGGAGGGCCGUUCAGUGAUGCUCACCUCCCAUAGCAUGGAGGAGUGUGAAGCGCUCUGCUCGCGCCUGGCCAUCAUGGUGAAUGGGCGGUUCCGCUGCCUGGGCAGCCCGCAACAUCUCAAGGGCAGAUUCGCGGCGGGUCACACACUGACCCUGCGGGUGCCCGCCGCAAGGUCCCAGCCGGCAGCGGCCUUCGUGGCGGCCGAGUUCCCUGGGGCGGAGCUGCGCGAGGCACAUGGAGGCCGCCUGCGCUUCCAGCUGCCGCCGGGAGGGCGCUGCGCCCUGGCGCGCGUCUUUGGAGAGCUGGCGGUGCACGGCGCAGAGCACGGCGUGGAGGACUUUUCCGUGAGCCAGACGAUGCUGGAGGAGGUAUUCUUGUACUUCUCCAAGGACCAGGGGAAGGACGAGGACACCGAAGAGCAGAAGGAGGCAGGAGUGGGAGUGGACCCCGCGCCAGGCCUGCAGCACCCCAAACGCGUCAGCCAGUUCCUCGAUGACCCUAGCACUGCCGAGACUGUGCUCUGAGCCUCCCUCCCCUGCGGGGCCGCGGGGAGGCCCUGGGAAUGGCAAGGGCAAGGUAGAGUGCCUAGGAGCCCUGGACUCAGGCUGGCAGAGGGGCUGGUGCCCUGGAGAAAAUAAAGAGAAGGCUGGAGAGAAGCCGUGGUGGUGAAA